GAUGACGUCAAACGCCGUGUGCUCACCCACGUGUGGUGCCCCUCUCCCGGUGUAGGCGCUGGAGCUGAGGACGCCUUUCCUGCGGGCGUAGUUGCUGGCUGCUCGGGCACUGGGACCUCGGCGGCUUGGGGACGCUGGCCGCGAAGUAGGGAGCGCAGGUGGCCGCUCGGGGUGAGGGCCCUGGGUCAUGGAGCACUUCUUGCUGGAGGUGGCAGCCGCGCCGCUGCGGUUAAUCGCAGCCAAGAACGAGAAGAGCCGCAGUGAGUUGGGCAGGUUCUUGGCCAAGCAGGUAAGACGUGAAG